GGAAACGCCUGGGCUGCACCGAGCUGGCGGUGGCUACGGCGACGGGAGCCGGCGGCGCUGCGGGUCAGCGGUCGCGUAGGACCCAGCGGACUCGGCAGCCUGGGGCGCCCGGCGGAGCUGAACCGCGGCCCCCGGUGGUGGGCUCAGCCGGUCGAGCUGCGCGGGAGGGUCUCACUGUCACCUUGGCUGGAGUACAGAGGCGCAAUCUCAGCUCACUGCAACUUCCACCUCCCUGGCUCAAGUGAUCUCCCACCUUAGCCUCCCAAGCAAAUGAAGAUAAAACAAUGUUCGCCAACCUAAAAUACGUUUCCCUGGGAAUUUUGGUCUUUCAGACUACCAGUUUGGUUCUAACAAUGCGUUAUUCCAGAACUUUAAAAGAAGAAGGACCUCGUUAUCUAUCUUCUACAGCAGUGGUUGUUGCUGAACUUUUGAAGAUAAUGGCCUGCAUUUUAUUGGUCUACAAAGACAGCAAAUGUAGUCUAAGAGCACUGAAUCGAGUACUACAUGAUGAAAUUCUUAAUAAACCUAUGGAAACACUUAAACUUGCUAUUCCAUCAGGGAUCUAUACUCUUCAGAAUAAUUUACUGUAUGUGGCACUAUCAAAUCUAGAUGCAGCUACUUAUCAGGUCACGUAUCAGUUAAAAAUUCUUACAACAGCAUUAUUUUCUGUGUCUAUGCUUAGUAAAAAAUUGGGUGUAUACCAGUGGCUGUCCCUAGUAAUUUUGAUGACAGGAGUUGCUUUUGUACAGUGGCCCUCAGAUUCUCAGCUUGAUUCUAAGGAACUUUCAGCUGGUUCUCAAUUUGUAGGACUCAUGGCAGUUCUCACAGCAUGUUUUUCAAGUGGCUUUGCUGGGGUUUACUUUGAGAAAAUCUUAAAAGAAACAAAACAAUCAGUGUGGAUAAGAAAUAUUCAGCUUGGUUUCUUUGGAAGUAUAUUUGGAUUAAUGGGUGUAUACAUUUAUGAUGGAGAACUGGUAUCAAAGAAUGGAUUUUUUCAGGGAUAUAACCGACUGACCUGGAUAGUAGUUGUUCUUCAGGCACUUGGAGGCCUUGUAAUAGCUGCUGUUAUUAAGUAUGCAGAUAAUAUUUUAAAAGGAUUUGCAACCUCUUUAUCGAUAAUAUUAUCAACAUUGAUCUCCUAUUUUUGGCUUCAAGAUUUUGUGCCAACCAGUGUCUUUUUCCUUGGAGCCAUCCUUGUAAUAACAGCUACUUUUUUGUAUGGUUAUGAUCCCAAACCUGCAGGAAAUCCCACUAAAGCAUAGUUGUAUACUAUCUUUAACUGGUUUUUCACGAUGGGGCACUAGGAAUCUCGACAUUAAUCUUGCACAGAGGACUUCUACAGAGUCUGAGAAGAUAUCAUCAUGCUGAAUCUGAUCAUACUGUUUUUUAAAAGUUUAAGGAUAAGACAUGUGUAUAUGUAACAAAACACAUUGCAUCUAGAAAUCAAAACUUGAAAGUAUUUCCAGGGAUUAGGAUUAGAAGGAAUAUUAGAGGAAACUUGAAAUCUGAGUUUAAAAAGAUUUUACCUUUUUGAUUGCUGCAGAAAUGUCCUAUGCACUCUUUGCAAGAGCACACAACAAAUGUCAGAUACCAAUUUUUGCAAAUUAGAUUUAAUCUUAUUAAAUGUUUUUAUCUUACUCUUUCUGUACAGAUAUAUCAAAUCACAUGAAAUAUUUAAAGUUUGAAAAUUAUAAUUACCUAUAAAGCUGUGAAAAAUAGAAGUAUAAUUUGAAAAAACAUUUCACUUAUCAGAGAUUUUUAUAUUUAUACAAAAGAUUACUAAAUGAAGGAUUGCUAAAUGUUUUUGGUUCAAUUACAUAAAAAUUAAUAUUCUGGGUCUGAUCUGUCAGAGAAUAAAUAUCAAAUCUAAAUUUAAUGUAGAGAUACAUACUAUUUCUCCAUAUGAAUUUUAAGAUAUUUUAGUGCUUCAAGACUGCUGAAAGCAAUCCAGUUGCUCCUGUGCUAGAUGGUAGCCAGAGAAUUUUAUAGUAAUGGAGGUUAGCCCUUAAUCUCUUCAUUGCAUUUCAUUUCUGUAAAUCAGAUUAAGUCCUUAAUAUUAUUUUAAAUUAAAAUUUGUGUGUAAUUGCCAUUAAAUUUUCAAAAUGUAAUUUAAAAGGAUUAAAUACUCAUUUAAUAAUUUAAAAUAAUUAUUGUAUAAUAUCUACAUUUGGAGAAUUUUGAACUAUCAAGCAUAUACUGUAUACAGUUAGAAAGUUAUUAAAUGAACAUUUUACUCAUUGAUCUGUAAAAACUUCUUUAAUCUACAACUGUUUACAAAAACAACAUUCAAACAAAUAGUACAGAUGUCAGUGACAGAACAAAAUGACUUUUCUUGGAGACAUUCCAGAUUGCCAUAUUACUUUAUUUUAAACAGCGCUAUGACUUUAAAUCCAAGGCUGCUCGGAAGAUUUUUUUAGGUCUCUCAUAAGCCUAUUCUUCCCUGAUCACAUGAGUGGGAGAGGUAGCCAAAUUUUGAAUUCCCUUUCUGUGUUCCCACAAGAGCUGCUGAGAAGGCCUGGCGCAGUGGCUCACGCCUGUAAUCCUAGCAGUUUGGGAGGCUGAGGCAGGUGGAUCACAAGGUCAAGAGAUUGAGACUAUCCUGACCAACAUGGUGAAACCCCGUCUCUACCAAAAAUACAAAAAUUAGCUGGGUGUGGUGGCACGCACCUGUAGUCCCAGCUACUCGGGAGACUGAGGCAGGAGAAUCACUUGAACCCGGGAGGCAGAGGUUGCAGUAAGUGGAGAUCACGCCACUGCACUCCAACCUGGGCGACACAGUGAGAGUCUGUCUCAAAAAAAAGAAAAAAAAAAAAGCUACUGAGAAGGAGCCACCAUUUUGCUUUAAAAUAGUGGGUUUUUUUCCUUUUUAAUGAACACUGGAGCUGAGGAUGCAGAUUACAUGAGUUAUUUAAUAAGUUGAUUCAAGAGAGAGAGAGUAUAUUAGAAAUGGUAAGAUGAUUUGGUGGGCAAAAAUGCUUUCUAUAAUUUGAAUAUGGGUUUAAUUUAAUUAUUAACUAUAGACAGAAUUACUUACUGAGUAUAAGAAGUAUUUUACUGUCUGGGCACAGUGGCUCAUGCCUGUAAUCCCAGCACUUUGGGAGGCCGAGGCGGGUGGAUCACAAGGUCAGGAAUUCGAGACCAGCCUGGCCAGCAUGGUGAAAUCCCAUCUCUACUAAUAAUACAAAAAUUAGCUGGGCAUGGUGGUGCGCGCCUGUAGUCCCAGCUACUCAGGAGGCUGAGGCAGGAGAAUUUCUUGAACACACCAGGUGGAAGUUGCAGUGAGCCAAGAUCGUGCCACUGCACCCCAGCCUGGGUGACAGAGCGAGACUCCGUCUCAAAAAAAAAAAAAAGAAAACACACACACACACACACACACCCACAGUAUGAAUGAAAAAAAUAAAAUACUUCUUUUUUUUUUUUUUUGAGACAGAGUCUCACUUUGUCGCCAGGCUGGAGUGCUGUGGCGCGAUCUCGGCUUACUGCAACCUCCCACUCCCUGGUUCAAGGGAUUCUCCUGCCUCAGCCUCUGAGUAGCUGGGAUUGCAGGCGUGAGCCACUGCGCCCGGCCUAUACUGUAUAUAUUUUUAAAGACUGUUCUAAUAGAUAUAAAAACUGUAAAAAAUAAGUAUUUUUAUAUAGCUCUCAUGGAUUUUAUUAAACAGAAUUGGCUCAAAAAUACUAUGUUACAGACUGUUGGGUACCCUUGCCUAACGUGAACUGGCAGUGUUACCUUGCUUUUGCAGUAAUAGUCUACAGAUUGCAGGUCUCAUCAAUUCCAUCCAAAGUUUAAAAGCAUUUAAAAUUACCAAAUCUUUAAAAUCACUUUGGUGGUGAUUCCAAAUUGGUACCAAGCAAACUUUCUGGAUGCCCAACAUGAUUUUCAGUAACCACCCUUUAGAGUAUUUGUUUACUAAGUUCACCACAUUUUGAACAUGGUAGUUUUAGACUGCAAUAAUAUUUAGACUUACAUUAUUACUUACUGCUAAGUAAAAUCUAAAUCCUGCAAAUGCACAGAAUUCAAGCUGAAAUAUAAUGAUUUAUGUUUAGCUCACAUUGAAGUAUUGGUUGGUUACUUAUGUAUUAAUGCAGUGUGCAUUCACAUUUAAUCAGGUUUAGUCUGUUUCUAUUUUAAUAAUUUUAAAAAAUUAUACAAGCAAAUUAGAUAUUAGACAUGUUAGUUACAAUGGUAACACAUUUUUAGGUGUCGAAACACAAUUUUCAAAAUUCCUAAUGAAAGUUAUAAAAAUGUAAACAAGAAUUGUAAAAAUGGACAAAGUAGUCAAAUAUAUUUUCAAAGCACAAUUUUAUUAGACAGGCAUAAUUUACAUUUUGCUUUUCUAGUGGGUUUGAAAAUGUUUAUUGGAGAUUGGGCUAUGUAGUUUAUAAUUUUUAAUUCAUAAAAAAGUAAUCAUACAUGAGAAGGUAGACCUGUGCCCUAGGAUCAUGUCACAUAUACAGAUAAUGCCAUUUCCUUGUGUGUGUGAUGUGUGUUUUGAUGACCUCCACAGGCCUUACUGUAUCAAGCUUUUAUAAUGAUGACUCCUUCAUUAUUUAAAUUCCUAUACUUUUUAUUUGUUAUCACGCAACUACUUUGUUCAAUGUGAAAAUGUGCUAACUCAUGGGAGAAGAGUGCCAAUUGAUAGUUCUUUUAGCAAUUAAGAAUAUGGUAUUUGGGAAGAAAAGUUUGAAAUGCAACAAAUGGAUAUUUCAACACAGUAGUAUUAUAUUAUCAGUUCUUUAGUAAGUGAUUUUAGAGAUGUUGUAGGCUACUUUUACGGUGGAAUAUAUAGUAUAGAGAUGCAAAACUUAAAUGUUUACAUCAAUUUAUAUUGAAUGUCACAUAAUUUCAUGGAAGGAAAGGUAGCUUGAUAUUUAGAUUCUAAGAUAUAAUCUGAAAGGAAACUAAUUAUGUUCUCUACACUUACUGUAAUACUGAUUAUUCUUACAUAUCAAAUUAUUGAACUUUAAAAAUUUCAUUGUAUAGUCAUUAAACUGAGUUGGGUUUUUUCUUAAAGGGUUUAGCAUCACUCAUUUGAUUUACACAUUCACAUUAUAAUAUUUAAUUAUCAUGGGUGUAUGCUUUACAUAAAAAAGGUUUAUAAAAGUUAUUUAUGCUAUAUUGAAAGUCAUCUUAAGAAUCUCCAGGUUAUUUAAAGUAGUUAUAGGAGCAGAGAACAAGCACCUUUAUCAAAAUCUGGUCCUAUGUGCCUUGCUUUACCAAAUACCUGAUUUUUCUGGAGGGUGUUCCUGUAAUUCACAACUGUAGACACAUGGGCAAAAUUAGGAUUUUUAAGAAUAAAUACAUUUCUAUUUUUUUGGUUGUUUCAACAUUAGCUCUUCAAAUUCAUUAACAAAAUUAAAAUAGGUAUAUUACAAAAGCAUAAACAUUUGUGAACAGUACUUAAAUAAAUUGUGAUACUAUUGCUCCAUCAUUGAACUUUUUGAAACUUUAACAAUUGUAUAAAACUGUCAGUUUGUUGUUUCAUUUGUAAUUACAAAAUAAUUUAAAAACUUUUUAAAAUAAUUUGGAUCCUGACUUUGUCUAUAUCUGUAUUUCAUUUGUUUAGAAAGAUUCUUUUGGGUUUGAUAAUGUAAUUUGUAUAUUUAAAUUUUUUAUGGACAUAAUUCAAAGGAAUGUAUAAAUUGGUCUUUUGUUAAAUGGCUUUUUAAUUGAUAAACUUCUCUUGUCAUUUUUUGGUAUCCAGCUAUUACCUAUUUAAUAGAUUUAUUGAAAUAGAUUAUUUUCAUAAAGAACUCUAUACAAAUCUUUUUCUAUAUUUCCUUAUUUUCCUAUUUACCUGUGUCUAUGACCUAACCUAUGAAUUAGUCUUCUCUCUUUAUAUAUCAAAAAUGAAUUACUGAUCUUUUUCUCUGGCUCUGUAGUAUCUCUAUCACUGUCACAUGUGAUCUUUCUUCCUUUUCUCUAGCCCAUAUUCUAGCAUGAAAUACUGGGUUGGCCAGGUGCAGUGGCUCAUUCCUGUAAUCCCAACACUUUAGGAAGCCAAGGCAGAAGAAUCGCUUGAGCCCAUGAAUUUGAGGCCAGCCUGGGCAACAUAGCCUUGUUUCUACAAAAAAUCUUAAAAAUAAAAUUAGCCAAUAUGUGGGCAUGCACCUGUGGGGCCAGCUACUCAGGAGGCUGAGGCAGAAGGAUUGCUUGAGCCCAGCAAUUUGAUGCUGCAGUAAACCAUGAUGACACUACUGGACUCUAGCCUGAGUGACAGUGAGACUCUGUCUCAAAAAACAAACAAAACAAAAACUGAAACAACAAAAAAAGACUGGGUUUAUUUAAGCUAGUUAGAAUUUAUCUUUCUAUAUGUUAAUAACAGCCUAACAGAUUUUUUGUUUUAAAUAUCUCUAGGCUAGCCUCAAGGUUAAGUAAUUAUAGAAGUUUGGUAUGUAUUUUCUUCAUAAUUUGAAUAUAAUUGCUUCCAUUGUGACUGUCAAUUGAAUGCAUGGAGAUCAAUUGUGAUAAUAUACAGGAUUUUAGUCCUAUCUCUACUGCUGAAGUAACCUUACACAAAAUACUUUGUAAAAAAAUCACUAAAGUGCCAGCAUUUUUAAAGUGUAUAUUUUUCUUUGGCAACCUCUCAUGAAAAGCACUAACUAAAAAUAUUUAAUAAUCUUUUUUGUAUUACAGUGCUUCUUUUGUUGGAAAUAUAUCACAAUCCUCAAGUUCCACUGCUAUGCAAAAGUAUCUUAGAAUCUGAAUCUUAUAGAUAAUACUACCUUUUUUUUUUUUUUUUUUUUUUUUUUGAGAUGGUGUCUCGCUCUGUCACCUAGGCUGCAGUGGUGUGACCUCACUGCAACCUCUGCCUCCCAGGUUCAAGCAAUUCUCCUGCCUCAGCCUCCCUAGUAACUGGGAUUACAGGCCAUGCCACCACGCCCAACUAAUUUUUGUAUUUUUAGUAGAGACAGGGUUUCACCAUGUUGGCCAGGCUGGUCUCAAACUCCUGACCUCAGGUGAUCCGCCUGCCUCGGCCUCCCAAAGUGCUGGGUUUACAGGCGUGAGCCGCUGCGCCCGGCCAAUACUGCCUUUCAAAAGAGACUGAUAGUGACCAGCAUUAGUAAUCAUACUGGUGGGGUUUUUUGGGGUGUUUUUCUGUUUUGUUUUUUGUUUUUUGUUUUUGAGACAAGGUCUUCCUCCCGUUGCCUAGGCUGGAGUGCGGUGACACAAUCUUGGCUCACUGCAGCCUUGAUAGAGCAAGCUCAAGUGAUCCUCCCAGGAGCCUCGGCCCCCAAGCAGCUGGGAAUACAGGUGCGCGCCACCAUGCCCAGCUGAUUUUUGUAUUUUUUUGUAGAGAUGGGGUUUUGCCAUGUUGCCCGGAUUGGUCUCAAACUCCUGAGCUUCAGUGAUCUGCCUGCCUUGGCCUCCCAAAGUGUUGGGAUUACAGGCGUGAGCGACCACACCCAGCCCAUAUUGGUCUUUCUUACUGUUCUUAAAAAGAGAAUUCCUUUAAGGCAGGACCGAUUACAUAUACACUCUAGAAAAGAAAAUAGCAAGGAAGAAAUAAAUUGCCUUCAAUUACCAAAGAUUUGAGCUUCUGCUAUGGCUGAGAGUGUUUUGGUCAUUGCAAAUUCAGGGGUUUCCCAAGUUCACCCUCAGUUCUGGCUAGAAAGAGAAAACUUACUAAAAGCUAUUAUACUCACAGUCAUAUUUAUUACAGAGAAAGGAAAUACAAAUUAAAACCAGCCAAAGGAAGUGACACAUAAAACAGAGUCUAGGAGUGGUCCAAACUUGAGGCUUUCGGUGUCCUUUUCUUGUAGCGUCAUGGAAGGUGUUAUCUACUCCUGACCACAAUGUUUGACAGUACACACAUAGUAUUGCCAUUCAGGGAAGCUCACCUAAGCUUUGGUGUCCAGAUUUUUAUUGAGAGAGGCUCUAUUAGUUGGCAUGGUUGGUUGAUUUUUUUGCCCAUGUAGUUGUCCUCUCUUUCCAACAUCUGCCCCUCCCUGGAGAUCUGGUUGACAUCAAGACUUCAGGGCCUCACCAUAGGUUAUCUCGUUAGCAUAAACUGUCAAGUGUUGUCUAAGGAACCCACAAUGAAUAAUAAAGACAUUCCUAUCAGUGAGAACUCCCAAAGACUUACACCAGAACUUUCUUUGGAUGGGCCAAAUUUCUUACUACACAAAGACCAUUCAUCUCUAUACACUUCCUUCUGAAUUGAUGAGGAUGAUACAAGCAACGACAAUUCUUCUUUUCAGAGACUUUUAAUUUUUUUUUUUUUUUUUUUUUUGAGAUGGAGUCUCGCUCUGUCACUCAGGCUGGAGUUCAGCGGCACGAUCUCUGCUCACUGCAACCUCCGCCUCCUGGGUUUGAGCAAUUCUCCUACCUCAGCCUCCCAAGUAGCUGGGAUUACUGGUGCUCACCACCACGCCCAACUAAUUUUUGUAUUUUUGGUAGAGACGGGUUUUCACCAUGUUGGCCAGGCUGGUCUCGAACUCCUGACCUCAGGUGAUCUGCCGGCCUUGGCCUCCCAAAGUGCUGGGAUUACAGGCAUGAGCCAUCACACCCAGCCCAGAGACUUUUAAUUUAUACAUUGUCAUUUUUAAUUUUAGAAUAUCUGUCAAAUGAUUCUGAACAUAACAUGAAUCUAGUGUGGAAAAAUGUUUAUAAUCAGAUAUUGUGUUAAGAACAUAUAUAUAUAUAUAGAGAGAGAGAGAGCAUAGUAUUGUCAUUUAGUUUUCACUUCUUAUGUUUAAUGACAACUUUAUAAAUGCUGGACUAUUUUAAACUACAAAUUUAAAACAUGGUUUAUAAACCUUUUACCUGUACUGCAUAUUAAUAAACAAUUUUGAACUAAUUUUAAAUUAGGCAUUCCUAUCACCAUUAUAAGGAAGAGCUAAAACCUGAUACCAGUUGUUAUUUUGGCUCACAGUAGGGCUUCACUAGUGUUAGGAUCACAUUUUCCUCCCUUGGACCUGAGAAUCAGGUGUUUUUCGUUUAAUGCAUUUAUUUUCAUUCAUUCAUUUAGGAUUUCUAAAAUGUUAGAGGUAAUUUGUUUAAAACAAAUAACAUGGUGUUCUUUUGGAAAUAUACAGUUUAUCUUAGAUAUACACUUUCCUCAUUUUAAAGGUAGAACUCACUGCAGGUUUAAAAGAAUAAUGAAUAUUGUUACAGUGUUUAGUGAUAAUCACUGAAAAUUCACGUUAAAAUAUACUUUAAGCUUGUCCAACGCGCGGCCUGCAGGCUGCAUGCAGCCCAGGAUGGCUUUGAAUGUGGCUCAACACAAAUUUGUAAACUUUCUUAAAACAGUAUGAGAUUUUUUUGCAAUUUUUUAAAGCUCAUCAGCUAUUAUUAGUUACUGUAUUUUAUAUGUGGCCCAAGACAAUUCUUCUUCUUUAAGGGUGACCCAGGGAAGCCAAAAGAUUGGACACCCCAGCUUUAAAUGUAGAGUAUUUAAGAGGUUCAGUUAAAUGUACUAAAUCAGACUUGUGUGAUUUAGACACAAAAUCUGUGUGUGUGUGUGUUUGGUCUUUUAAAAGAUACUGCAUGUACAAACAUGAUUUCUAAUAAUUGAGGGUUUAUUAAGUUUUUCCCUUUAGGCUAAAGUUUUAUUUUAUUCUGCUUGGAUAGUAAAUACAGCAUUUUAAAAUGAUGAUGCUAAGUGCUUUUUUAAUAUAUGCAUGCUGCUUCAAUAGGUCUUUUAAAUAUAGCCAAGGCAGGGUAAUAUUUCCUGAGUGAUGAUAGAAUUAUAGAAAAUCAUGAAAGAUGUGUGCCCAUGUUUCAUUUUAUAACUGUUCCAGUCAUAUUGCUAUGAAUUCUAGAAUUUUAAAACCUGCCACACUUAUUUUGGAUGUUAUAUACACAUAAUGCCUCAAAUUUCCAUUAUUUCAUAUUAUUUUUCUCCAUUUCCCUCGUGUCAAGUUUCAUUUUGUUUUCAAUGUUUUGUUUUUAUAAUAUUGCCAUUUUAAUGGCUUCAAUCAUGCUAUGACAGAUUGUGCCAAUUUAGCUUUAAAAAACUCAUGGGCUACCUCCAUGAACUCACACAUGCGGCAUUGUUAAAGAACCUUUUUUAAAAUUAAAUUUUCUCCAGCUUUUCAUUUUGCAGCAUACAAAAAAAUUGAAAAAUUGGUAUACCACCUAAAUCCAACCAUUAUUAACAUUUUGCCACACUAGCUUUAUCUCUGUUGGGACACUUUACCCCUACAUACUCCAGCAUGCGUGACCUAAAGAUAUGGACAUCUUCUUAAUUAACCUCAGUGCCAUUAUGACACCUAAGAAAAUUUAAAUUAAUUCAGGUCACUUCAUCUAAGUUCAAAUUCAAAUACAAUUGCCCCUCUGUAAACGUGGGGGAUUGGUUCCAGGACCCCCACCUCGUGUAUACCAAAAUUUGGGCACACUCAAGUCCUUAAGGGGAAACCGCGUAUAAGAAAAGUCAGCCCUCCCUAUGGGUGGGUUUCACAUCCUGCAAAUAACUGUGUUUUCCAUCUGCAUUUGGCUGAAAAAAAAUCUGCAUAUAAGUGGACCCAUGCAGUUCAAAUCUGUUGUUCAAGAGUCAACUGUAUUCCCAGUUGUCUCAAAAAUGAUUUUUUAUAGCUUUUUUGUUUUGGAACGAGGGUAAAAUCAAGGUUAAUGCUUUGUAUUUGAUUGUCUCCUUUGGUCUUGAAGUCCCCUUCCUGCACCACCACCUGCCCCUCAAUGGCUUUUUUAUACCAAGAGACUGAAAAUGCUACCUCUAAUGACUUUUCUCCCCAUGAUAGUACUCUUUGAAGGACCAAAGUUACUUUGCUCCUAUUAUGUGGUUUGAUUUGUUCCCUUUAUUCCUUUCAUGUCCUUUGAACUGGAAGUCAAGUCUAUAGGUUUGAUUACCUUCAGGUUAAAUGUAUUGGGUAAAAAUAUUUCACAGAUUUUAUAUUGUAUCAUAUUAAAAGGCACAGAUAAUCUCAUUAUUAAUGUUGGUAAUUAUUUGGUUAAGAUGAUGACUACCCCAUUGUAAAGGUUAUUGUAAAGUUCUCCCUGUGGUAAAGGUCAUUUGUUCACCCUUAGUAAUCUAUGGAGUAAUGUUUUAGCACCAGGAGAAUAUUCUGUUUCCCAAUGCCUUUAGCAUCAAUUGAUGAUUCUUGACUGAAUCAUUUAUUACACUGGGGUGCAAAAUGGUGAUAAAUUUUUUUUAGUGCUCUAAAUUUCUUCUACAUUUAUUAGUUUAUAUUCUUUUUUAAAAUAAAAAAGUAUAUUUCCCUCCUGUUUCUCUAAUAUCCCUCUUUAAAAAAAAGACCAUGUCUUCAUGAAUUUAAAAAAAAUUACUCAAUAUAUUAUAGCCAAUCGGUCACAGUUCUUUUUGAUGCUCAUAUAUAUUGUGAGCCUCUAGCCCAUGUAAGUCACAGCAAGCUAGCUCUUGGGUUUUUUUUGAGAUGGAGUUUCACUCUGUCACCCAAGCUGGAGUGCAGUGGCACGAUCUCGGCUCACUGCAACCUCCACCCUCCGGGUUCAAAUGAUUCUCCUUCCUCAGCCUCCUGAGUAGCUGGGACUAUAGGUGCCUGCCACCGCGCCUGGCUAAUUUUUUGUAUUUUUAGUAGAGAUGGGGUUUCACCAUCUUGGCCAGGCUGGUCUUGAACUCCUGACCUCGUGAUCCACCCGCCUCGGCCUCCCAAAGUGCUGGGAUUACAGGCAUGAGCCACCGCGCCCGGCCACUCUUGUGUUUUUUAAACAUGACCACAUUAGUCUUUUAGUCCUUAUUUGCUUUAGGCACAAGAAAUCUGAGGCUUACCUUAUAUUUGUCUUGUUCCAAAUUUGGAUUAUCAGCUAAUUCUCCAAGGAGCCCUAUACCUUUUAAGGGGAGUGGGAUUUAUUUAAUUUUUUCUUUGGAGUCCUUCUAGCCAGUGAAUGGAAUUUAUUAUAGAAUCCAUUGUUACUGAGCUGUCAUUGUUUCUAGGCCAUUUUAGUGGACAUAGCUAGGAAAUACAAUUUUAAAAGAUCAUGAAUUCAAAUUAAUAUUUACAACUAAAAUUUAGCAACAUGGCCAGGUGCAGUGGCUCAUCCCUGUAAUUCCAGCACUUUGGGAGUCUGAGGUGGGAGGAUCACUUAAGGCCAGGGGUUCAAGACCAGCCUGGGCAACAGAGUGAGAUCCUGUCUCUACAAAAAAAAAAAAAAAGAUAAAUUUUUUCGAAAAGUUUUAUAUGAAAAGUGUACUCUGAAAAAAUCUAGCUGUCAUACCUAUCCCUCCAUUCCUAACCAUCUCUUAUAAGUAAUUAUUAUCCAUCUCUUAUAAGUAAUUAUUAUAAGUAUUUUCUUAGUUUUCCAAUUUAUCUUUCAUGUGUUUCUUUUUAAAAAGCAAACAAAUAUGCAUAUUGCUGUACUUACUGUGCCUCUUUCACAACAUGGGGUCUUUAUAAAAUUUCUUUGGAUGUUUAGAAAGGUUUGUAUGCUCUAAUUUAUACUGAUAACAUUUUAUAUAAUGCAUUUAGAGUCCCCAAUUUGCUUGUCUAGGCCUCUACUAUUUAAUUUGACACCUUUAAAUGAUGUUCUUUGACUCUUAUCUAAUUGUCUAUGUGACCGUCAGUGAAUAUAUUAUCUGUUCAUAUUUUCUGUAGUCUUAUUUCUUUUUGAUUAGAACAUAUAAUAUUUACACACUAUUUUCCCAUCCUAAUCCCCACCUUUGUAAUAAAAUUAAUUAAAAUUUUAAAAAAGUAUAUUUAAUAACCUACUGAUACUUACCUGAAGUCUCUCUGGUCAACUUUUGGCUGGAUGAAGCUCUUCUGUAGAGUAUUCAAGGAGGGCUUGUAAGUACUGUACAAUAUUCUCUGAGUUGUGACAUGUUUAAAAUUUCUUCUGGAGCCUAGAUACUUAAAGUACACCUUGGCCAUGUAGAAAAUCCUUGACAAACAUUUCCUUUUCUUGAGUUUGUCUGAAUUUGUGCUUCACUGUUGGGUUGCUUGAUGUUAUCAUCAAGAAGUGUGGCACCACUUGAUUUUUUUCCCUUUUGGAAAUGACAUUUUGUUUGUUGUUUUUUACCUAGAGACCCAGAUAAUUUUUUCUAUAUUAUUUUAUCUAUGAUCCUUUUUAUCUCAUUUUUGUUCUCAUAGCUGUUUUAUUCCUCUUCUCUGUAUUUCUUACUUUACUUUUAUUUGUGUCUCUCAGGUACCCUGUGAUUUAGUUUUCAUUUUUAGAUGAUUUUAUCUUUUCAGUAUAUUGCCUAUGUUUGUUCAACUCUCAUUUUACAUCUUACUAUUGAGUUUAAAAAUUUUUAUUUGCUGUGUUCUUUUAUAUGUGCAAUUAAUGAUAUUCAUGUUGGAGUGUUGUAUAUUAUUUGCCUCUGCUUCAUAUUGUCUAGAGGGUAGUAUUUUCUAUUGAUUGAAAAGUUUUCAUUUUCUGUUUUUUAUAAUAGCCUUGUAUGGAUUUUUGGUGGCUUUUCUAUUCAUGAUUAAAUGUGUAGGAUCUUCUUCAAUCAGCAAUAACAGGUGGCUCUAUAGAAUGGAGGGUAGAAGGGAUGUGGGUGACUUACUCAGUUUUUAGUUAAAGAGGACCCUCUUCUGUUAGCAUGGUGAAGUGCAGUUUCUUUAAUAAAUUGUGCAUGGUGGGGGUGGGAUUUGGAUUCUGUGAUACAAUCUUGUUUCUUUAGGAAUCUUUUACUUUUGGCCACUUGCCUUUCUUUCCAAGGAAUCCCACUCCCUUUCAAGGUGCCUCAUGAACUGUUUUCAUGAACUUUCCAAACAUUGGUUUCUGCUUGUUUCUAAGCCUGAUUCUUGGCCUUCUCAUUAAUUUUCAAAACUUCCAAUAUCCUUCCAAAUAAUUCCCUUUUGCUUACGUUAGCGAGUACUAGUUUGUUAGCCAGUGUUAGUUUCUGUUGAUCCUAACCAAAAAACCCUAACUGAGAUAUCAGUCUCUUAGCGCAAAGUUUGUGAAUACGGUCAUCCCUCCAUAUGAGGAGGGGAGUGGGAAUUGGUUGUGGGACUUCCGUGGAUAUCCAAAUCAGUGGAUGCUAAAGUCCCUUACAUAAAAUGGCAUAGUAUUUGGUUAUCAUCCUCCCCAUACAUCAUCUCUAGAUUAUUUAUAGUACUUAAUACAAUGUAAUGCUGUGUAGUCAUACUGUAUUUUUUACUUGUAUUUUUGUUGUUUUGUGGGAUUUAAAAAAUAUUUUUAUUCUGAGGAUAGUUGAAUCCACAGGAUACUGAGGGCCAGCUGUAUUCACAACCCAAAUCACAUACAAAGCGACAAGUUCAUACACAAUAGGCCUAUUAGAACAGGACUGUUCUCUCUUGUUUAUCAUUGCAGCCUUUCUAGCACAAAGCCUGGGACAUUCUGGACAUUUAGUAUGUGUUAAAUUUCUCUUACUACAUUAUUUCCAACAGUAUUUACUGCAAUCUGCAAUUACCUUCCUUUUGUUUUGUAACUGUGUCCCCCACUAGAAUGUAAGCUCUGUGCAGAUAGUGUCUCAUUUAUUGAUGUAUCCCUGGCAUCUAAUAAAACACUGACAACACAA